AGUUCUAGAACGUUGCUGUGGUAGCGCUCGGGCGCCAUGUUAGGACGAAGGGGAAGGAGGAGAAGCGCUUAAAGCGGCGGGAGCGGUGCGGGAGAGGGGUUGGACCCAGGGCUGAGGCAGGCCCCCCCCUCCCUCCCGCCUCAGUGGAUCAUGCCCAGGGCGGCAGCGGCGGCGGUUGCGGGGGGGAAGUGACUGGGCGGUGCCGGCGCCGGAGACGAUGCCGUUUCCAGUUACAACACAGGGAUCACAACAAACACAACCGCCACAGAAGCACUAUGGCAUUACUUCUCCUAUCAGCUUAGCAGCCCCCAAGGAGACUGACUGCGUACUUACACAGAAACUAAUUGAGACAUUGAAACCCUUUGGGGUUUUUGAAGAGGAAGAGGAACUGCAGCGCAGGAUUUUAAUUUUGGGAAAACUAAAUAACCUGGUAAAAGAGUGGAUACGAGAAAUCAGUGAAAGCAAGAAUCUUCCACAAUCUGUAAUUGAAAAUGUUGGAGGAAAAAUUUUUACAUUUGGAUCUUACAGAUUAGGAGUGCAUACAAAAGGUGCUGAUAUUGAUGCGUUGUGUGUUGCACCAAGACAUGUUGAUCGAAGUGACUUUUUCACCUCAUUCUAUGAUAAGUUGAAAUUACAGGAAGAAGUAAAAGAUUUAAGAGCUGUUGAAGAGGCAUUCGUACCAGUUAUUAAACUCUGUUUUGAUGGGAUAGAGAUUGAUAUUUUGUUUGCAAGAUUAGCACUGCAGACAAUUCCUGAAGAUUUGGAUCUACGAGAUGACAGUCUGCUAAAAAAUUUAGAUAUAAGAUGUAUAAGAAGUCUUAACGGUAUGAGAAAGCCUACUUCCUUUUGUGUACUUCAGUUUUUGUCAGAUAUUAGUUGUUUUUACACAAGUUUUGUAUUGAAGCUUUUUAUAGCUAUAUUGUUAACACAGUAGUGAGUUAAAUAAAAUGAACUUUGCCUAAUAAACUACAGAAGAGUAUGUAGUAGUUUAUUUCACUCUACAGUAUUUUAUACACUGUAUUUCUUCUGUCAUUAAUGGUAUACUCAGGACACUUAAAAAGACCAUCUGACUUUUGUACUCUGUUGCUAGUGAUUUAGGUUUCAUGGCCUAACCCAAAUUAAUUUUGAUCCUGUUAUUCUUUAGUAAUGCUUUCAGCAUUGCUGAGAUCAGAAGGACUACUUUGGUACAAUUUUAUAUUAGCAUAGCUUGUUACUGUGCUCUUGAAGAGCAGUUCUUGGAAACUUUAGUGGAUUAAGUCUUCCGCAGUAUAUGUGGGAAGUUUUAAUUGUGAAUCUGAAGUUCAAAUUGGGGCAGGUUACAGUUUACUUUGGUUUCUUUGGUCAGUGCUUACAAUAGGAGAUAAAUGCUUUAGAUUUUUUCCCCCUCUUUAUUGAAUUAGCUUUACUGGUUCUACCAAAUAAAAAUUUAUGUUUACUUUUAACUUCAAUCUCAGAAAAUUUGGAAGCAUUACCAUUAAACUUUUGAUGAUUUAAUGUUGUUUUUUUUUGUUUUGUUUUGUUUUGUGUGUGUGUGUGUGUGUGUGUUUUUUUUUACCCCUAUUAAUUAGGUUGCAGGGUAACCGAUGAAAUUUUACAUCUAGUACCAAACAUUGACAACUUCAGGUUAACUCUGAGAGCUAUCAAACUAUGGGCCAAACGUGAGUUCAGAAUUUGUUGGCUAGCUUAUUAAAAAUGUUCAAACUUUUGUUCAACACUAACUUAUCUUUUUGCUUUUCCCUUAUCAACAGGCCACAACAUCUAUUCCAAUAUAUUAGGUUUCCUCGGUGGUGUUUCCUGGGCUAUGCUAGUAGCAAGAACUUGCCAGCUUUAUCCAAAUGCAAUAGCAUCAACUCUUGUACAUAAAUUUUUCUUGGUAUUUUCUAAAUGGUAUGUGUUUAGAUUAUAUUAAAAUAAAAUUGAUUGUAGACACUGAAGUUUAGUCUUAUUUCUAUGACAUUUCUCAGCUUGGUUUCAGAUUCAAAUUUUAGUUCAUGAUGUAGUCAUGUAGGCAGCCUUGGAGAUCACAUUGUGUAUAAAAUGGCAAACUGAAACUAUUUUUUUUCCCUAGUUUGGCCAGGAUAGUAAGGCAGAUUCUAUUUGUACUUCCUUGCAUAAACUUACCCUCUGAAUAAACUCUGAAUUUUAGCAGCUAAGAUCCAAUUUAUUGAUAGGUUGGGAAAUCAGUUACUAUACUUUUGGAUAAAACUUGUACACACUACCUCUUUCACUCUUUUAAUUCUCUAUCUAUAGGCCAUUAGUUUCUUGUGAUUGUUUUUUUUUUCUUUUUGCUUUCAGCAUUUAUUUGGCCUAAUAUUAAAGAUACGAAUUUUCAUAAGAAGCUUUUAAAGAAUAAAUUAACAUUAAGUGCUUCGGGACAAAAAAGGAAUUUGAGAUUAGUCAUUAACCCAGAUUUUUUUAAGUUUCUUCGUUUCAUUUCCACAUAUGUCAACUAUGAUUUAAGAAAAAGUAGAAUAAAAGAUUACUGCCAUUUUAUAUUAAUUGCCUUGGCCCAAAAGGUGAGGGUUCUUGGUUUUUAAUCAAAUUAAGAUAAAUCGUCCAUUCCUGUUCUUAUGAACUCCUGCUCCUCCCUCUGCAAAAGAGAUGUUCUUUUCUAGUAAUUUUAUAAAAAUUAGUUAUUUGAGACAAUUUAGAGCUGUGUUCAACUGGAGGAAAAAUAAAAAAAAUUUAGAACCAUGCCACACUUUUCAGUACACAUUCUGGCUGUUUUGGGAUUUAGUAGCACUUAUAAUCAGGUGUGAUAAGAUUAAAGAAUGUCAGAAUUUCUUUUUUUUUUUUUUUUUUUUUUGUUUGAGACGGAGUCUCACUCUGUCACCCAGGCUGGAGUGCAGUGGCACGAUCUUGGCUCACUGCAAGCUCUGCCUCCUGGAUUCAUGCUAUUCUCCUGCCUUAGUCUCCUGAGUAGCUGGGACUACAAGCGCCUGCCACCACGCCUGGCUAAUUUUUGUAUUUUUAGUAGAGACGAGGUUUCACUGUGUUAGCCAGGAUGGUCUCGAUCUCCUGACCUCAUAAUCCGCCCGCCUCGGCCUCCCAUAGUGCUGGGAUUACAGGCGUGAGCCACCGCGUCCGGCUGUCAGAAUUUCUUUUAAUGCUACACAUAUAUAAGCAAAUAAUGUUUUUAAGAAGCUAACCUUGAUGUUAAGAGUGGCAGGUGUUCUCCAGUUUUUACCUCUUUCAUAUGGGACCAAAGUAGCUAGUUUAUGGAACACAUAUGAAAAUGUGGUUAUGCCACCAAGUUUUACUACUACACUUGUCUUACCACUUUUAAGUCAUGAAUUCUAUAAUUAUUCAUACCCCUUUGCCUGUGAUCAGAAGUAACUUUUAAAAUUAUCACUUGACUUUGGAUGGAACUAGUAUAAAGGCAGGAAUUUUGUCUUUCAGUGGAGAUUUAUUCUGUUCAAGGUUGAAGUGGACACAUCAUUAUCUUGGGAUGGUACUUCUUUAUUUAAAUAGUCCUUUAAAGUUCUUUGAGUGGCAGAGAACGUUUUUGGUUUCAGUCUGAGAAGGCUACCAAAUGGUUUAAGUUCAUUUCAUAGUUAGGAGAAAAAGAUUUUGAGUAGUCUAAUGUCGUCAGAAAGGAUUAAAACGUUGUAUGUACCAAGAAGGCAGAAUGAAGAAGGAUCACGUUCACAAAUGCUGUAUGUUUAACAAAAUACGUUUAGAUGGUAAUAUCCAAUAGUCUUAUCAAGUGCUACAAUCUUUUUAAACAGGGAAUGGCCAAAUCCAGUGCUAUUGAAACAGCCUGAAGAAUGCAAUCUUAAUUUGCCUGUAUGGGACCCAAGGGUUAGUGUAUUAUUUUUUCCCCUACCAAUUCACACUGUGCAAUAACAAGUAAAAAUCAUCUGCAUAAACUCCAGGGAGACUUCCAGCCUUUUACUUAUGAAUGGUCAUGUCCGUAUUACACUUUCUUUUAGAUAACCUCAACUAUAAUUGUCCUCAACUAUAAUUGAUGUGAGAAGCAUAAUUAUGUACCCUGUAAACCACAUUUAAUUGUACAUAGUUUUUAAUACAGAUUUUACUAACAUUUUAAUUUAUUCUAUAUAGAACUACCUUGUAAGUCAAAGUUGUGUGGGCAUUUGUGCUUUAAAAAAAAUAAAAGGAUACUAAAAAUCCCUGUAUUUUUUAUUUUAUCUAAGUAUUAUGCUAAAGUUGGGUUGUUAUAGGAAAGCUGUUACUUAAUGUUUACAUGUGGCAUAUAACUUCUAAGCAUUUUCACUUUAAUUACCAUGAUGUAAUUGUAAAAAAAAUUGGUUUAGAUAUUUUAGAGAUUAUAAAAACAUGGUUGGGCUAAAGAAGACCUUCCAUUCUGUUUCUUGGGAAGUUACAACAUUUACCGCUUACUCAUUUUAAAUGUUAACAACAUGCACUUUAUAAACUGAUAAAAGAAAUUUAGGUUUGAAUAAGAUUUCCUAAGUUUAUGAAAUCCUUUUUUUCUAAAUUAUUACAAUAUCAAAAAUUUUAAAUUCUGUUGAAUUACAUCAAGCUAUGCAUUUUCAGGUUUUCCGAACCUCAAGGCAUUUACUUUUAGAGGAUGUGAAUUUACAACUUACUUUGUGGAAAUGUGCCACUUACUGAUAUACAGAUUUAAAAUUAACAGUAUAUCAUUUCAUUAUCUCCUAACAUAUCAACAUGGAUAAUGUAGUUUCACCGCGUGUUAAUAAGCUUGAACUCCUUAAUAGUUUCAGGGUAUAUUAAGAACUUAAGUUUCUAUCUUGUUGAAAAUUAGCUUACAAAACAUUGUAGCAUGACAUGUCUCUAAAGGUAAUUGUAUGUGCAUCCCCAUUUCUGUUGUUGAAUAAAGAAAAACUAAACAUCAA